AUCCGAGCGGGUUUGACGGAAGGAGCGGCGGCGACGGAGGAGGAGGAUGGAGGCGGUGGUGUUCGUCUUCUCUCUCCUCGAUUGUUGCGCGCUCAUCUUCCUCUCGGUCUACUUCGCCAGUUGCAGUGGCUGACACCUGUCCCCAGUACUUUGGGAGGCCGAGGAGGGAGAAUCACUUGAGCCCAGCGGUUCGAGACCAGCUCUGGUAACAUAGGGAGACUUCCUCUCUACAAAAAUAAAACAAGAGGAAAAAAAAAAGAAACAUGUUUCAGGUCUGUGUCUGUGUAAUACAAAGAUGACUGCAGCCUACAGUAAGAAAUCCAGAGACUGAAGGCUAUAGCUUUAGGGAUCUGAUAUGGAUCGCAGAGUAUUAGUAUAACAUCAGCUGACAUUUUAUUGAGUGCCUACUUUGCAUGUGGCUUACAUGUUAUUUCAUCUAAUUCUCUACAACAACUUCGUGAGUGGGUAAUUCCAGAAUUGAUUGGCCAUACCAUUGUCACUGUAUUACUGCUCAUGUCAUUGCACUGGUUCAUCUUCCUUCUCAACUUACCUGUUGCCACUUGGAAUAUAUAUCGAUACAUUAUGGUGCCGAGUGGUAACAUGGGAGUGUUUGAUCCAACAGAAAUACACAAUCGAGGGCAGCUGAAGUCACACAUGAAAGAAGCCAUGAUCAAGCUUGGUUUCCACUUGCUCUGCUUCUUCAUGUAUCUUUAUAGUAUGAUCUUAGCUUUGAUAAAUGACUGAAGCUGGAGAAGCCGUGGUUGAAGUCAGCCUACACUACAGUGCACAGUUGAGGAGCCAGAGACUUCUUAAAUCAUCCUUAGAACCGUGACCAUAGCAGUAUAUAUUUUCCUCUUGGAACAAAAAACUAUUUUUGCUGUAUUUUUACCAUAUAAAGUAUUUAAAAAACAUGAAUUGAGUUUCUGUAGAUUUCUAGUUCUCAACUUUAGCCUGAACGCCAACACUUGAAGGUGUUUUUCAUCCUCUGUAUGUUGAAGGUGGUUAUUUGUAUGUAGGAACAGGACUGCCAUCCCAGCUUUGCAUGCCAAAGAAAUAAAGAACACACUUUAAAGGGCAAACUGAAGAGAUGAGCGAGCAAAGGUGCCCUUCAGGUCUACUGAAAAGUUAGAGUACAAAACAACACUGUUGAUCUGGACAAAAGAAGAAAAAUUACCCUUUUUGCUUGUGUUGUGACAACUUCAUUUAAUAUGGUUUAAAGAUUUAUGAGACUGUCAGCUAAAAGUCUUUUCACAAGAAUGUCAACAGAGAAUGGCAUCUCAAAAUAUAUAUAUUUCUUUGCACAAUUUGUGAAACCUUAUAAGCCAUUUUCCCCAGGUACAAUGUAGUUCCUGCUGAUAGAAAGGAAAUAUUUUGUCAAGAGCUUUCAUUUAAAAGCUACUACCUCCACAAUCACCCCCAAACCCAGAAAAUCCCCACUGGCUCUUGCCAGUCUGGUUUUCGUAUUGCAGUUAUUCCAAUUGUAUUUGAUCUCCCUGAUAACGUAUUUUCAUGGGUUUGGGUAGAAGAUGCUAAUCAGAUUAGAAGCAGGAAUAGUUAUUUGCUGUCUGUGAAAUUGAGCCUUUUGGUGCGCCACGUGGUGCCAGAUCAACACUUCUAUCCCUCUGCACUGACCACGUUGUGAACUGGGAGACCAAAUGCAAGCCAUUUCAUGGACAUAGCAAUAUACAACCAAACUCUGUUCCUUGGAGUUAUAUUGUAAACUCUUGCAGGUGGGAGAGCAGUUCACCUCCUUAGCUCUGUUUGCCAGCUCUUACAGGGUAAAAUAAACCUGGCAAUUUAUCCUCAGUCCUAGUUUGUGGUUUAAUGUUGCUAUCUUAAGCACUGGCAUUUGGGCAAAACAUGACUGUGUUCUGUGGGAGAAUCCAAAGGCAUUAUUCACUCUAGUUGAGAUAGAAUUGGGUGGCUAAACAGGGUGUGUGGUACCCAAAAGAUUAAAUGUUACAUGUCCUUUUAGUCCUUGACCAGGUCUAGCCUUGGCAGAAGCAAGGGAGCCACUAAGCCAAACUCCCUGUGCAGACAGACCAUGUUUCAAGGCUGGAAGUAGUGCCCUGGCAACACACAAAAGGAACGGUGAAAUGGUAGGCAAAGUGAACUUGGCUCUGCUGGCCUCUUUGGGGUCACAGAAAUUGCUCCUUGUGGUAAUCUUAUAUUUCUGUCAGGCACAGGGCCAAGAAGCUGUGUAACAGACAUUACUUUGCUUGCAUCUCUUUUUCAUACCUUUUCCCUCUGAGGCAGCUUUUGCUUAGAAAACAGUCCCUUCACUCUGCCUUUCCUCCUAACUUCCUGUGCCUCUUCAUGUUCUGCUCAAGCUUUUUAAAGCAACGAAGCUGUUGGAGAACUUAAAUCCUUGCAACUGAGAGAUAAGCUACUUAAAGGCGGUAGAGAUCUUUUUUUUUUUUUUUUUGAGAUGGGGUCUUGCUGUGUUGCCCAGGCUGGAGUGCAGUGGUGUGAUCUCAGCUCACUGCAACCUCUGCUUUCUGGGUUCAAGCGAUUCUCCUGCCUCAGCCUCCCAAGUAGCUGGGAUUACGGCUAGCUACUCCUGGCUAAUUUUUGUAUUUUUAGUAGAGAUGGGGUUUCACCAUGUUGGCCAGGCUGGUCUCAAACUCCUGACCUCAAACGAUCUGCCUGCCUUGGUCUCCCAAAGUGCUGGGAUUAUAGGUGUGAGCCACUGCGCCUGGCCAUGUAGAUGACUUUUGACCAAAAUGUUUCACCUUCUCAUUCAGAUAUUCUUAGUAACCAAAACAGUGACUCAUGCAGUUGAGAGAGCCUUUGGGCUGUCAGUUUACAGUACAUCAGGCUUGCUGAGGCUAAGCAAAUCAGAAAGGUGCCAUGUUUAUAACAGAGGUCAAAGCUCCUUACUUCUGAAACAUUAGCUGUGGUUAAAAACAAAAACUCUUCCUUCUUGUAUUGCUUGUCUAUCAAAGCCAGGAAAGUGGGGGAUCACUGUAGUUAAAUUUUUUUUUUUUUUAAUUAGAGACAGAGUCUUGCCCUGUCGCCCAAGCUGGAGUGCACUGGCGCAAUCGUGGUACACUGCAGCCUUGAACUCCUGGACUCAAGCAGUCCUCCUGCCUCAGCUUCCCAAGUAGUUGGGAGUAGGUGCACACCACCAUGCCCAGCGAAUUUUUUGUAGAGACAGAGGUCUUGCUAUGUUGCCUAGGCUGGUAUCAAAAUUACUGGCCUCAAGCGAUUCUCCUGCCUCGGCCUCCCAGAUGUUGGGAUUACUGGUGUGAGCCACCACGCCCAGCUCAAAAACAAUUUUUUUAGGGGCACUUCUACAAAUCAUGAAAGGGGGAUAAAAGCACUGACUUUAAAAAGCCAUGUUUAAGAUGCUAUAAAUGUUCUCCCCUUUUCAUUGAUUGGAGAGUUGUAGAGGACCUUAGAGAUCAUUUUGUCUAACUCCCUCAUCCCAAAGAUAAACUGAGGCCUAGAGAUCGUUCAGGGUGUUGUAACUGGGAACAUCUGAAUGCUGAGGCCUAGAGAUCGUUCAGGGUGUUGUAACUGGGAACAUCUGAAUGCUGAGGCCUAGAGAUCGUUCAGGGUGUUGUAACUGGGAACAUCUGAAUGCUGAGGCCUAGAGAUCGUUCAGGGUGUUGUAACUGGGAACAUCUGAAUGCUGAGGCCUAGAGAUCGUUCAGGGUGUUGUAACUGGGAACAUCUGAAUGCUGAGGCCUAGAGAUCGUUCAGGGUGUUGUAACUGGGAACAUCUGAAUGCUGAGGCCUAGAGAUCGUUCAGGGUGUUGUAACUGGGAACAUCUGAAUGCUGAGGCCUAGAGAUCGUUCAGGGUGUUGUAACUGGGAACAUCUGAAUGCUGAGGCUUAGUCCAGUGUUCUCUCUCCCUUACCACUCCUCUUCCCCUUCCCUCUAUAAUGGCAGUACCCAGGGCCCGGUCCAUAGACUACUAUCGAGUGCUCCUAUGUGCAUCUUAGUACGUAUCAUUUUCCCUUGCCUUUUUCCUUCUAUCCUUUCAGUGGUAGCAACUGCCCUUGCUAAUCACCGUAACCUCGGCUGAGAAAGAAGAGGAAGCGAAAUCCAAGAUGCAGCUCAGUUCAUCAAAGCCUAGCAGGUCCCCUCAGCUGCCUUUUCAUGCCUGCCACAGACUACAGUAGGACAAAACCUGACCUGGUCUUUGAAGUUAAGAGCUAAGAAAGCUUCCUAUAGUAGUAUCUCCCAUGGCACUUACCACAUUCUAUCUGGUAUUACAGUUAUUUGUAUGCAAUUAAUCACUCUUAGAUUGUAUGUUCCUGGAGGGCAGAAUAUGCCCAUUCAUAUUUGUAUCUUCUUCCUUCUGCUCUUGGCACCUAACACAGUGCCUUGCACACAAACAAUAAAUGAUUGUUGAGUGAAUAAGUAAA